GAACCGCGGCUUAGGUGGCGGCGGCGAAGGAUGCACCCGGCAGGCUUGGCGGCGGCGGCUGCGGGGACGCCCCGGCUGCCCUCGAAGCGGAGGAUCCCUGUGUCCCAGCCGGGCAUGGCCGACCCCCACCAGCUUUUCGAUGACACAAGUUCAGCCCAGAGCCGGGGCUAUGGGGCCCAGCGGGCACCUGGUGGCCUGAGUUAUCCUGCAGCCUCUCCCACGCCCCAUGCAGCCUUCCUGGCUGACCCGGUGUCCAACAUGGCCAUGGCCUAUGGGAGCAGCCUGGCCGCGCAGGGCAAGGAGCUGGUGGAUAAGAACAUCGACCGCUUCAUCCCCAUCACCAAGCUCAAGUAUUACUUUGCUGUGGACACCAUGUAUGUGGGCAGAAAGCUGGGCCUGCUGUUCUUCCCCUACCUACACCAGGACUGGGAAGUGCAGUACCAACAGGACACCCCGGUGGCCCCCCGCUUUGACGUCAAUGCCCCGGACCUCUACAUUCCAGCAAUGGCUUUCAUCACCUACGUUUUGGUGGCUGGUCUUGCGCUGGGGACCCAGGAUAGGUUCUCCCCAGACCUCCUGGGGCUGCAAGCGAGCUCAGCCCUGGCCUGGCUGACCCUGGAGGUGCUGGCCAUCCUGCUCAGCCUCUAUCUGGUCACUGUCAACACCGACCUCACCACCAUCGACCUGGUGGCCUUCUUGGGCUACAAAUAUGUCGGGAUGAUUGGCGGGGUCCUCAUGGGCCUGCUCUUCGGGAAGAUUGGCUACUACCUGGUGCUGGGCUGGUGCUGCGUAGCCAUCUUUGUGUUCAUGUUUCCCCUUUUGCCGGGCGCGGUGGCUCAUGCUUGUAAUCCCAGCACUUUGGGAGGCCGAGGCGGUCGGAUCACGAGAUCCGGACGCUGCGGCUGAAGAUCUUGGCAGACGCAGCAGCUGAGGGGGUCCCGGUGCGUGGGGCCCGGAACCAGCUGCGCAUGUACCUGACCAUGGCGGUGGCGGCGGCGCAGCCUAUGCUCAUGUACUGGCUCACCUUCCACCUGGUGCGGUGAGCGCGCCCGCUGAACCUCCCGCUGCUGCUGCUGCUGCUGGGGGCCACUGUGGCCGCCGAACUCAUCUCCUGCCUGCAGGCCCCAAGGUCCACCCUGUCUGGCCACAGGCACCGCCUCCAUCCCAUGUCCCGCCCAGCCCCGCCCCCAACCCAAGGUGCUGAGAGAUCUCCAGCUGCACAGGCCACCGCCCCAGGGCGUGGCCGCUGUUACAGAAACAAUAAACCCUGAUGGGCAUGGCGUGGACAGCCUCUCCUUGGCCUCGCGCACGAAUGGGCGGGCCCAGCGCUGGGCAGGGGGCAGGGAGCUGGGGACGGGCCAGAGUAGGCACCACGCUGACCAGUCGCAGAAGGCAGAGAGGAAGGUUUAAUGAGCCCUGUCCAGGGCCCUUCAGUGGGGAGCCUCCUUCUUCUUGCCCUUCUCCUUCUUGCCCUUCUCCUUCUUCUUCACUUUGGGCUUCUUGGCCUUGCCCGGGAUGCUCUCGUGCUGCUUGGAGCCAGCAGCGUGGGACUGUGGGGCCGAGGGCAGGGAUGGGAGAGAAGAGAUGGUUCUGGGCUGGAAGCGAGACAGGGGGACCACUCCCCGCACCCUCCCCGCCAGCCCCAGUGCGGGGACGCCUCUCUGGGGUGCAGGGCACGUGCUUGGGGACGCUGGCGAGAGCCCCUUACCUUCACAUCCGUGUCCGAAUCGCUGGAGCUGCUGCUGGAGUCGGAAGAGCUGUGGUGUCCUUGCUGGAUGGAGGUGCGGCAGUGAGGCGGCGCCCCUUACCCAGCCCCCUGAAGUUGGAGGCCUAAGGCAGGACCCUGGGGUCAGGGGCAACCCCAGCCUUCCCGCCCCUCCGCAGCCGGUGAUGAGGCGACUUACCUUUGGACCCGGACCUGCCCCUGCCUCCGACCGGCCCUGAACUUUGUGGGGACUGAGCUUGGGAUCUCCCCCGUGGCCCGCCCCCACACCGGGCUUCUGGGAGGUGGGCUCCAGGGCUGUGGAGAGAAGUUGGGUGGUUGGUGCAGGCAGCUUCUGGGCUUGAGUCCGGCCCCCUGCACCUCCAGUCCACACUCCCCAGGAGCUCACCUGCUCCCAGGUCGAACUCCAUGGCGGUAAGAGAAGUUGGGUCCUAAGGCCAAGGGCGCCUGGGCCCUGCAGAGGAGCGGAGCAGGGGGAGGAGCGCUGAGACCUGCCCGUUGGAGGAAUGCUGAGACGCCCCACCCAACCUCUGUCCUGGUCCUCAGCCCUGACUCAUUGCCCGGCACCACCCAGGAUUUCCUCUGUGAGAAGUGGGGGAGAUGGACAGGUGACUGCUUCCGCCAGCCUUGGUGCCUCAGGGGAGGCCGACUGAGGGGGGCUCUGUGGAUGGCAUUCGGGGAGCUACAGGUUUCCCCCAAAAGCUCAGAUGCUCGUUCUUGAAGAGGGAGGUGCUGCCCCUGCCUUCCUGCGUACCGCGACAAUACAGCUUCCUCCGCGGCGCUUUAACACGCAGGGCGCUGCUGCCAGGGGCGUCCCGUGUUCUAACUCGCUCCCACAGCCCCUCCGGCUUGGUGAGCAGCGUCUGAGGGGUGAGGGGCAUAGACUUGGAGCCAGCCUGCUGCACUAGAUGCCAGCUGUGUCACUUAGCAGCAAGGUGACCUCAGCAAAGUUGUUUUACCUCUGUGCCUCAGUUUCCUCAUCUGUAAAUAACAGCUACCCAUGGGAUUGAUGUGAAAGUCAGAGGAGUUAAUUUCCUAGAAUGGUGUCUGGCAUGAAGUACUGAUAAUGUGUUGGUUUUUUAAAAAAUAAAAGGUAGGUGUUUUAGGCCAGUCA